GUGACGCAGCCCGGGUCUCAGGGAACAUGGCGGCGCUGGUGAGACCCGCGAGGUUUGUCGUGCGACCGUUGCUGCAGGUGGUCCAGGCUUGGGACCUUGACGCGAGGCGCUGGGUCCGGGCGCUGCGGCGGAGCCCAGUGAAAGUGGUGUUUCCUUCCGGAGAGGUGGUGGAACAGAAGCGCGCUCCUGGGAAGCAGCCCCGCAAGGCACCAUCUGAGGCCAGUGCCCAGGAGCAACGAGAGAAACAACCGCUCGAGGAGUCCGCAUCCCGCGCUCCCAGCACCUGGGAAGAGUCUGGGCUUCGCUACGAUAAAGCUUAUCCCGGGGACAGGAGGCUGAGCAGUGUAAUGACAAUAGUAAAGUCCAGGCCAUUUCGGGAAAAACAAGGGAAGAUCCUGCUGGAAGGUCGCAGGCUCAUUUCAGACGCUCUCAAGGCUGGAGCUGUGCCAAAAAUGUUCUUCUUUAGCCGUCUAGAAUACCUAAAGGAGUUGCCAGUCGAUAAGCUGAAAGGUGUCAGCCUCAUUAAGGUGAAAUUUGAGGAUAUCAAGGAUUGGUCCGACCUCGUAACGCCACAAGGAAUAAUGGGGAUUUUUGCCAAGCCUGACCAUGUUAAGAUGACAUAUCCAAAGACUCAGCUUCAGCAUUCACUGCCUUUAUUAUUGAUUUGUGACAAUCUCCGUGACCCUGGGAACCUGGGGACAAUUCUGAGAUCUGCAGCUGGGGCAGGCUGCAGCAAAGUGUUACUCACCAAAGGCUGUGUGGAUGCCUGGGAGCCCAAAGUGCUCCGGGCGGGUAUGGGCGCACAUUUCCGGAUGCCCAUUAUCAAUAAUCUGGAAUGGGAAACCGUGCCCAAUUACCUGCCCCCUGACACUCGGGUCUAUGUGGCUGACAACUGUGGCCUUUAUGCCCAGGCUGAGAUGUCUAAUAAAGCUAGUGACCAUGGCUGGGUGUGUGAUCAACGAGUGAUGAAGUUUCACAAGUAUGAGGAAGAGGAAGAUGUAGAAACCGGAGCCAGUCAAGAUUGGCUGCCUCAUGUUGAGGUUCAGAGUUACGACUCGGACUGGACAGAGGCGCCGGCAGCUGUGGUGAUUGGCGGGGAGACCUACGGCGUGAGCCUGGAGUCCCUGCAGCUGGCCGAGAGCACUGGUGGCAAGAGGCUGCUGAUCCCCGUUGUGCCUGGUGUGGACAGCCUCAACUCGGCCAUGGCGGCAAGCAUCCUGCUUUUCGAAGGGAAAAGACAGCUGCGGGGGAGGGCGGAGGACUUGAGCAGGGACAGGAGUUACCACUGAGGACGCAGAAGUGACUUCUGCUUGAGGACGUCUGCAGCUCCUCCUACACCAGCACACUGGUGGGAGGCUGGCGGAGUCAGUGACUAUGGCCCCCACGUUCAGGAGGAAGGUGUGAUGCCGUCAUACAGUUACAGGAAAAAUAAGAACUUCCUCAGAAAGAACAGGUCCGAAUUCUUCCUGUCGCGUCACUGAUUUUGAGGUUCUUUUUUCUCUUGGUGACAAUAGGUGACCCACGUGGCUCUGUGUGUUUUUAAAAAUUGUCCACCAAGAAGCACUUUGUGCCCAGAAAGUUCCUGAAGCAUCAUCCUGGCAGGGAGGCGCCUGCUCCACCAGCUGGUGGGUGUUUGUAAUCGCCAAGCACCAGCUAUAGGUCACAGCCACAUCACUCACAGCUGAUCACUGGUUGGUGGAAAAUAAACUAUGAGCAGCAGAUUACGUUA